AACUGAGAACCGCUCUCGGCGCGGCGGCGGCUGCUAGGGCCUGCCGCAGCCGCGGCCACUCGGAAAGGGCGGGACUUCCCCGCAGGGCGGGGUGGGGCGGAGCGCUCUAUCAGUCCUCCCGGUCGCCCCACUGCGCAUGGCACGUUGCGUACUCCCCUCCCAGCAACCGGUCUGGCGGCGGCGCGGCAGUAAAACUGAGGAGGCGGAGCCAAGACGGUCGGGGCUGCUUGCUAACUCCAGGAACAGGUUUAAGUUUUUGAAACUGAAGUAGGCCUACACAGUAGGAACUCAUGUCAUUUCUUGUAAGUAAACCAGAGCGAAUCAGGCGGUGGGUCUCGGAAAAGUUCAUUGUUGAGGGCUUAAGAGAUUUGGAACUAUUUGGAGAGCAGCCUCCGGGUGACACUCGGAGAAAAACCAAUGAUGCGAGCUCAGAGUCAAUAGCAUCCUUCUCUAAACAGGAGGUCAUGAGUAGCUUUCUGCCAGAGGGAGGGUGUUACGAGCUGCUCACUGUGAUAGGCAAAGGAUUUGAGGACCUGAUGACUGUGAAUCUAGCAAGGUACAAACCAACAGGAGAGUACGUGACUGUACGGAGGAUUAACCUAGAAGCUUGUUCCAAUGAGAUGGUAACAUUCUUGCAGGGCGAGCUGCAUGUCUCCAAACUCUUCAACCAUCCCAAUAUCGUGCCAUAUCGAGCCACUUUUAUUGCAGACAAUGAGCUGUGGGUUGUCACAUCAUUCAUGGCAUACGGUUCUGCAAAAGAUCUCAUCUGUACACACUUCAUGGAUGGCAUGAAUGAGCUGGCGAUUGCUUACAUCCUGCAGGGGGUGCUGAAGGCCCUCGACUACAUCCACCACAUGGGAUAUGUACACAGGAGUGUCAAAGCCAGCCACAUCCUGAUCUCUGUGGAUGGGAAGGUCUACCUGUCUGGUUUGCGCAGCAACCUCAGCAUGAUAAGCCAUGGGCAGCGGCAGCGAGUGGUCCACGAUUUUCCCAAGUACAGUGUCAAGGUUCUGCCGUGGCUCAGCCCCGAGGUCCUCCAGCAGAAUCUCCAGGGUUAUGAUGCCAAGUCUGACAUCUACAGUGUGGGAAUCACAGCCUGUGAACUGGCCAACGGCCAUGUCCCCUUUAAGGAUAUGCCUGCCACCCAGGGUGAAGACUCUACGGUAAAAGGAAUUUGAUGCCUUGGAAAGGGAGAGCGGAAACUGUGAGCCCUGCUUUCCAGCCAUGGCGAAAGCGGGUACUUUUGUGCAACCCCUCUCCUUUCACGUUGGCCUGGCUAGGGCGGAGCUGCCACGCCAGUGACCAGCGUUUCUUUGGGAAAAUUGGACUUACUCCACUUCCACCUUUUCCACUCUUCAAAUGAUCACAUUUGCAUAUUGGGAACAGUGUAUUUGUGAAGAGACUCUCAGGCCUUCCAGGGACCACCCCCCCCCCCCACCCGCUACAGCCCAGGUCCUGGUUCUGUCCUCCCCAGAUGCUGCUAGAGAAACUGAACGGCACAGUGCCCUGCCUGUUGGAUACCAGCACCAUCCCCGCUGAGGAGCUGACCAUGAGCCCUUCGCGCUCAGUGGCCAACUCUGGCCUGAGUGACAGCCUGACCACCAGCACCCCCCGGCCCUCCAACGGUGACUCGCCCUCCCACCCCUACCACCGAACCUUCUCCCCCCACUUCCACCACUUUGUGGAGCAGUGCCUUCAGCGCAACCCGGAUGCCAGGUAUCCCUGCUGGCCUGGGCCUGGGCUUCGGGAGAGCAGAGGGUGCUCAGGAGGGUAAGGCCAGGGUGUGAAGGGACUUACCUCCCAAAGGUUCUGCAGGGGAAUCUGGAGCUACACACAGGAGGGAUCAGCUCCUGGGUGUGUCAGAGGCCAGCCUGGGGAGCUCUGGCCACUGCUUCCCAUGAGCUGAGGGAGAGGGAGAGGGGACCCGAGGCUGAGGCAUAAGUGGCAGGAUUUCGGGAAGCUGGGGACACGGCAGUGAUGCUGCGGUCUCUCCUCCCCUUUCCCUCCAGGCCCAGUGCCAGCACCCUCCUGAACCACUCUUUCUUCAAGCAGGUAUCGUAGCCCCUUCGUUCUGGUUCUGGUUCUAGUUCUGGUUCUAACAACUCACAAUCCCUUUAGCUUUCUCUCCCCUCCCUUUGAAUGAGAGAAACUACCCCGCUUCCGAAGCCCCUGAAAGACACUGCUCCUUCCUCUCAUGGAGUUGGCUCCGACAGCCCGUCUGCCACCAGGCCAUGGUUCCUUGCCCCAUGGUGUCCUGGGACCCAGAGCAACAGGAUCUGUCACCCACCUCUCUCUUCUCCCCCAGAUCAAGCGACGUGCCUCAGAGGCUUUGCCCGAAUUGCUUCGUCCUGUCACCCCCAUCACCAAUUUUGAGGGCAGCCAGUCUCAGGACCACAGUGGAAUCUUUGGCCUGGUAACAAACCUGGAAGAGCUGGAGGUGGACGAUUGGGAGUUCUGAGCCUCUGCAAACUGUGCGCAUUCUCCAGCCAGGGAUGCAGAGGCCACCCAGAGGCCCUUCCUGAGGGCCGGCCACAUUCCCGCCCUCCUGGGCAGAUUGGGUAGAAAGGACAUUCUUCCAGGAAAGUUGACUGCUGACUGAUUGGGAAAGAAAAUCCUGGAGAGACACUUCACUGCUCCAAGGCUUUUGAGACACAAGGGAAUCUCAACAACCAGGGAUCAGGAGGGUCCAAAGCCGACAUUCCCAGUCCUGUGAGCUCAGGUGACCUCCUCCGCAGAAGAGAGAUGCUGCUCUGGCCCUGGGAGCUGAAUUCCAAGCCCAGGGUUUGGCUCCUUAAACCCGAGGACCGCCACCUCUUCCCAGUGCUUGCGACCAGCCUCAUUCUAUUUAACUUUGCUCUCAGAUGCCUCAGAUGCUAUAGGUCAGUGAAAGGGCAAGUAGUAAGCUGCCUGCCUCCCUUCCCUCAGACCUCUCCCUCAUAAUUCCAGAGAAGGGCAUUUCUGUCUUUUUAAGCACAGACUAAGGCUGGAACAGUCCAUCCUUAUCCCUCUUCUGGCUUGGGCCCUGACACCUAAGUCUUUCCCACGGUUUAUGUGUGUGCCUCAUUCCUUUCCCACCAAGAAUCCAUCUUAGCGCCUCCUGCCAGCUGCCCUGGUGCUUUCUCCAAGGGCCAUCAGUGUCUUGCCUAGCUUGAGGGCUUAAGUCCUUAUGCUGUGUUAGUUUCGUUGUCAGAACAAAUUAAAAUUUUCAGAGACGCUGCUGGAGAA